UUUUUUUUUUUUUUUUUUUCCUUUGAGACAGAGUCUCCCUCUGUUGUCCAGGCUGGAGUGCAGUGGCGUGAUCAUGGCUCACUGUAGCCUUGACCUCCUGAGCUCAAGCAAUUCUCCCACCUCUCAGCCUCCUGAGUGGCUGGGACUACAGGAAUGUGCCACUGUGCCCAGCUAAUUUUUGUAUUUUUUAAAUAGAGACCCAGUUUCACCAUGUUGUCCAGGCUGGUCUCAAACUCCUGGUCUCAAGCAAUCUGCCUGUCUUGGCCUUCCAAAGUGCUGGGAUUACAGACGUGCGCCUGACCUUUUUUUUUUUUUUUUUUUUUUUUUUAGAGAUGGGGUCUUGCUGUGUUGCCAGGGCUGGAAUGCAGUGCUUAUUCGCAGGUGUGAUCAUAGUGUGCUACAGCCUCGACCUCCUAGGCUGAAGUGAUACCCACCUCAGCCUUCCAAGUAGCUAGGACUACAGGUAUGCCACUGCACCCAGACAGUGUUUUUGCAAAGCACAAUUUGUAAUUUUGGUGAAGUCCAGUUUAUCAGUUCUUUAUUUUAUGAACCAUGCUUUUAGUGUCAUACCUAAAAUCUCUGCCUAACCUCAGGUUACAAAUAUUUUUCCCAAUGUUUUCUUCUAGAUAACUUAUUUCUUUGCAUUUUAUAUUUUGCUCUAUGAUCCAUUUUGAGGUUUUUUUUUUUGUUUUUUGUUUUUUUAUAAGGUGUAAGGUUUGGGUGAAGGUUCUGUUUUUGCCUCUGGUUGUCCCAUUGCAACAAAACACCAUUUGUUCAAGAGACUAACCUUUCUUCGUUGAAUUGCCUUUAUUCCUUUGCCAAAAGUCAAUUGACUAUAUAUGUGUAAAGCUGUUUCUGGAUUCUCUUAUUUUGUUCCAUACCAUACAAUCUUGAUUAUUAUAGCUUUAUACUAUAUCUUAAAAUUAGGCAAUAUUGUUUCUCCAAUUUUAUUCUUUUUCAAAAUUAUUUUGACUACCCUAGUUCCUUUGCUUUUUCAUAUAUAUUUUAGAAUCAGUUUAUCUAUAGCUACAAAAAAUCCUUUUGGGAUUUGAUUAGGAGUGCAUUAAAUCUGUAGAUCACUUUAGGGAAAAAUGGACAUCUUUUCUAUGUUGAAUCUUCAAAUCUAUGAACACAGUAUGUCUUGCAGUUUAUUUGUGUUCUCUGAUCUCUUCUAUCAGCAUUUUGUGGUUUUGAGCAAAUUGCUUCUCUGUAUAUUUUGUUAGAUUUAUUCCCCACUAUUUCGUAUUUUUGUAGCUAUUGUCAAUAGUAUUUUUAAAAAUCUUGGUUUUCAGCUUUUCUUUGCUAAUAUAUAGAAAUUUGGUUCAUUUUUGUGUUGUCUUUAUAUCACGUGACUUUUUUUAAAUUAUACUUUAAGUUUUAGGGUACAUGUGCACAACGUGCAGGUUAGUUACAUAUGUAUACAUGUGCCAUGUUGGUGUAUCAUGUGACCUUUCAAACUGACUUAUUAGUUCUAAGACUUUUUAGUAGAAUUCUUGGUUUUUUCCUGCAUAGACAAUCUGUGUUGUCUGCCAAAAGGCAUAGUUUUAUUUAUUCUUUCCAAAAUGUAUGUCUUUUAUUUCUUUUUCUUGCUUUAUUACACUGGCUAUGACUUGUAGUCCACAGUCUUGAAUAGGAGUGGUGAGAGUAGACUUCCUUGCCUUGUUCUUGAUGUUAGGAGGAAAGCAUUCAGUCUUUUAUCCUCUAGUAUAAUUUUCACGGUAGAGUUUUUGUGUAUGGGAGGCUGCAUGUUUUAUUUAUUUAUAUAUAUAUAUUUUGAGACAGAGUCUCACUUGUCAUCCAGGCUGGAAUGCAGUGGUGCGAUCUCAGCUCACUGCAGCCUCCGCCUUCCGGGUUCAAGUGAUUCUCCUGCCUCAGCCUCCCGAGUAGCUGGGAUUACAGGCAUGUGCUACCACACCGGCUAAUUUUUUUUUUUUGAGACGCAUCUCGCUCUGUUGCCCAGGCUGGAGUGCAAUGGCGUGAUCUUGGCUCACUGCAACCUCUGCCUCCCGGGUUCAAGCAAUUCUCUUGCCUCAGCCUCCUGAGUAGGUGAGACUACAGGCACCCGCCACCGUGCCCAGCUAAUUUUUAUGUGUUUAAUAGAGAUGGGGUUUCAUCAUGUUGACCAGGAUGGUCUCCAUCUAUUGACCUCGUGAUCUGCCUGCCUCGGCCUCCCAAAGUGCUGGGAUUACAGGCGUGAGCCACUGCGCCUGGCCACACCCGGCUGAUUUUUUUGUAUUUUUAGUUGAGACGGGGUUUUGCCAUGUUGGCCAGGCUGGUCUCUAACUCCUGGCCUCAGGUGAUCCGCCCACCUCAGCCUCCCAAAGUGCUGGGAUUGCCGGUGUGAACCACCGCGUCCAGCUGCAUGUUUUACUUUUUAGUUUUGUUAGCUUUUAAAUUUUGAAGUAAUAUGUAGUCAUACACAUUUCAAGCAAUAAUUUGAGUCACUUUAAAGGAAAAAAGAAAGAACCUACUAAAUUUUAAAUCCUUAACCUGUUAGGAUUAUUAACAAAUGUCUGAUAUUAAGGCAGUGGGAGUUGUUAGAUUUCAGUUGUUAAAUCAGUAGCUUCUUGAAGAUUUCUUGAAUAAAUACUUAGUUUUGGCUUAAUCUGGAGAUAUUUUCAACAAACAAAAUAAUCAUAGGGAUAGGGAGGGCAAUUAGUUUGUUGUAAAAUAUAUUUAUGCUUAAAAUUUUUGAAAAAUGGCUCUCAAGGUGUCUUGUGUUUUCUAGAGUCUAGUUUUAUUCUACUGUUCCUUUGUUUUUAACUUGUAAUAUUGUUUAGUAGAAAACUUUCUAAUAUACCAAAAAUUUCAGUAAAUGGAACUUAAAAAAUGUAAACCAUUCCUGAUUUCAUCUUGUUUGUUGACAACUUGUCUCAGAUAUUAAGAUUUUAUAUUAAACUGCAGACUUUCUUUAACAUUAAGGAUUUUGAUUUUCCUUGAACCUUGAUUGGAAAAUAGUUUAGAAUACUGCUAUAAUUGGUAAAAUUUGAGGUGAGAAAAAUAACUUUAGCAAACAUAUACUGAGUAUCUAGAGAUAACUUGCAGUUUUAGCUUCUUUACUCUCCCUGAGAUUUUGGGAUUUUAAUAAUCUAGAAAGCCACAACUCCUUACUGUCUUUGUCAGUUUGGAUUUUUAUAACAAGAUAUUAUAGACUAGAUGGCUUCAACAAUAGACAUUUCUUUCCCACAGUUCUGAAGGCUGCAGGCUGGGAAGUCCAAGACCAAGAGGCCAGCAGAUUUAAUACCUGAUGAGGGCCCGCUUCCUGAUUUGCAUACAGCUGCCUUCUUGCUGUAUGGUCUCAUGGCUGAGAGAGAUCAUUGUCUUUUUCUUGUAAGCGCAGUAAUCCCAUCAUGAAGUUCCCACCCUCAUGACCUGAUUACCUCUGGAAGGCCUCACAUCCACAUCCAUCACAUUGGGGAUGAGAGUUUCAACAUGAAAUUCAAUAUGAAUUUUAGGAGAAACACAAACAUUCAGUCUGUAGUACUUUUGACAUAAUGCUUUCGUGAAAACUUGUUAGAAAGUUGAAUGUCUAAAAUUUGUCCCAUUGACUUAUCUAUCUUAUAUGGGAGUUCUUUCACUCCAGAGAACUAAAAAUUAUAAAAUGUCUAAUUAUGGUUUGUGCAGGUGUUGCCUCUUGGGUCCAGACUGCCUGGCUGGUGGGUGAUAACCAGCCCAAAUAUUCUUGCCAACCAGUGCCACCUGUGGCUCUGCAGGGAAGAGCGGGAGAGAAGAACUCAGGUGCAGGUGGUCAUGAAAGGGAGGUUGAGUUGGUUGUUUCACGAAGAAAUCCAGAGGAUGUCCAGGAGAUAAUUGUAUGGAAGAGAUACAGUGAUUUUAAGAAACUACACAAAGAACUAUGGCAAAUUCACAAAAACUUAUUCCGACAUUCAGAGUUGUUUCCUCCAUUUGCUAAAGGAAUAGUGUUUGGGCGAUUUGAUGAAACUGUUAUCGAAGAGAGAAGACAAUGUGCUGAAGACCUGCUACAGUUCUCUGCCAAUAUUCCUGCUCUUUACAAUAGUAAACAGCUUGAAGACUUUUUCAAGGGUGGAAUAAUUAAUGAUAGUUCUGAAUUAAUUGGUCCUGCUGAAGCUCACUCAGAUUCCCUCAUUGAUACCUUUCCUGAGUGUAGUACGGAAGGCUUCUCCAGUGACAGUGAUCUGGUAUCUCUUACUGUUGAUGUGGAUUCUCUUGCUGAGUUAGAUGAUGGAAUGGCUUCCAAUCAAAAUUCUCCCAUUAGAACUUUUGGUCUCAAUCUUUCUUCGGAUUCUUCAGCACUAGGGGCUGUUGCUUCUGACAGUGAACAGAGCAAAACAGAAGAAGAACGGGAAAGUCGUAGCCUCUUUCCUGGCAGUUUAAAGCCGAAGCUUGGCAAGAGAGAUUAUUUGGAGAAAGCAGGAGAAUUAAUAAAGCUGGCUUUAAAAAAGGAAGAAGAAGACGACUAUGAAGCUGCUUCUGAUUUUUAUAGGAAGGGAGUUGAUUUACUCCUAGAAGGUGUUCAAGGAGAGUCAAGCCCUACCCGUCGAGAAGCUGUGAAGAGAAGAACAGCCGAGUACCUCAUGCGGGCAGAAAGUAUCUCUAGUCUUUAUGGGAAACCUCAGCUUGAUGAUGUAUCUCAGCCUCCAGGAUCACUAAGUUCAAGGCCCCUUUGGAACCUAAGGAGCCCUGCCGAGGAGCUGAAGGCCUUCAGAGUCCUUGGGGUGAUUGACAAGGUUUUACUUGUAAUGGACACAAGGACAGAACAGACUUUCAUUUUAAAAGGUCUAAGGAAAAGCAGUGAAUACAGCAGGAACAGAAAGACCAUCAUCCCCCGCUGUGUGCCCAACAUGGUGUGUCUGCAUAAGUACAUCAUCUCUGAGGAGUCAGUAUUUCUUGUGCUGCAGCAUGCGGAAGGUGGCAAACUGUGGUCAUAUAUCAGUAAAUUUCUAAACAGAAGUCCUGAAGAAAGCUUUGACAUCAAGGAAGUGAAAAAACCUACACUUGCAAAAGUUCACCUGCAGCAGCCAACUUCUAGUCCUCAGGACAGCAGUAGCUUUGAAUCCAGAGGAAGUGAUGGUGGAAGCAUGCUUAAAGCUCUGCCUUUGAAGAGUAGUCUUACUCCAAGUUCUCAAGAUGACAGCAACCAGGAAGAUGAUGGCCAAGAUAGCUCUCCAAAGUGGCCAGAUUCUGGUUCAAGUUCAGAAGAAGAAUGUACUACUAGUUAUUUAACAUUAUGCAAUGAAUAUGGGCAAGAAAAGAUUGAACCAGGGUCUUUGAAUGAGGAGCCCUUCAUGAAGACUGAAGGGAAUGGUGUUGAUACAAAAGCUAUUAAAAGCUUCCCAGCACACCUUGCUGCUGACAGUGACAGCCCCAGCACACAGCUGAGAGCUCACGAGCUGAAGUUCUUCCCCAACGAUGACCCAGAAGCAGUUAGUUCUCCAAGAACAUCAGAUUCCCUCAGUAGAUCAAAAAAUAGCCCCAUGGAAUUCUUUAGGAUAGACAGUAAGGAUAGCGCAAGUGAACUCCUGGGACUUGACUUUGGAGAAAAAUUGUAUAGUCUAAAAUCAGAACCUUUGAAACCAUUCUUUACUCUUCCAGAUGGAGACAGUGCUUCUAGGAGUUUUAAUACUAGUGAAAGCAAGGUAGAGUUUAAAGCUCAGGACACCAUUAGCAGGGGCUCAGAUGACUCAGUGCCAGUUAUUUCAUUUAAAGAUGCUGCUUUUGAUGAUGUCAGUGGUACUGAUGAAGGAAGACCUGAUCUUCUUGUAAAUUUACCUGGUGAAUUGGAGUCAACAAGAGAAGCUGCAGCAAUGGGACCUACUAAGUUUACACAAACUAAUAUAGGGAUAAUAGAAAAUAAACUCUUGGAAGCCCCUGAUGUUUUAUGCCUCAGGCUUAGUACUGAACAAUGCCAAGCACAUGAGGAGAAAGGCAUAGAGGAACUGAGUGAUCCCUCUGGGCCCAAAUCCUAUAGUAUAACAGAGAAACACUAUGCACAGGAGGAUCCCAGGAUGUUAUUUGUAGCAGCUGUUGAUCAUAGUAGUUCAGGAGAUAUGUCUUUGUUACCCAGCUCAGAUCCUAAGUUUCAAGGACUUGGAGUGGUUGAGUCAGCAGUAACUGCAAACAACACAGAAGAAAGCUUAUUCCGUAUUUGUAGUCCACUCUCAGGUGCUAAUGAAUAUAUUGCAAGCACAGACACUUUAAAAACAGAAGAAGUAUUGCUGUUUACAGAUCAGACUGAUGAUUUGGCUAAAGAGGAACCAACUUCUUUAUUCCAGAGAGACUCUGAGACUAAGGGUGAAAGUGGUUUAGUGCUAGAAGGAGACAAGGAAAUACAUCAGAUUUUUGAGGACCUUGAUAAAAAAUUAGCACUAGCCUCCAGGUUUUACAUCCCAGAGGGCUGCAUUCAAAGAUGGGCAGCUGAAAUGGUGGUAGCCCUUGAUGCUUUACAUAGAGAGGGAAUUGUGUGCCGCGAUUUGAACCCAAACAACAUCUUAUUGAAUGAUAGAGGACACAUUCAGCUAACGUAUUUUAGCAGGUGGAGUGAGGUUGAAGAUUCCUGUGACAGCGAUGCCAUAGAGAGAAUGUACUGUGCCCCAGAGGUUGGAGCAAUCACUGAAGAAACUGAAGCCUGUGAUUGGUGGAGUUUGGGUGCUGUCCUCUUUGAACUUCUCACUGGCAAGACUCUGGUUGAAUGCCAUCCAGCAGGAAUAAAUACUCACACUACUUUGAACAUGCCAGAAUGUGUCUCUGAAGAGGCUCGCUCACUCAUUCAACAGCUCUUGCAGUUCAAUCCUCUGGAACGACUUGGUGCUGGAGUUGCUGGUGUUGAAGAUAUCAAAUCUCAUCCAUUUUUUACCCCUGUGGAUUGGGCAGAACUGAUGAGAUGAACGUAAUGCAGGGUUAUCUUCACACAUUCUGAUCUUCUCUGUGACAGGCAUCUCCAGCACUGAGGCACCUCUGACUCACAGUUACUUAUGGAGCACCAAAGCAUUUGGAUAAAGACCGUUAUAGGAAAUGGGGGGGAAAUGGCUAAAAGAGAACAAUUCGUUUACAAUUACAAGAUAUUAGCUAAUUGUGCCAGGGGCUGUUAUAUACAUAUAUACACAACCAAGGUGUGAUCUGAAUUUAAUCCACAUUUGGUGUUGCAGAUGAGUUGUAAAGCCAACUGAAAGAGUUCCUUCAAGAAGUUCCUCUGAUAGGAAGCUAGAAGUGUAGAAUGAAGUUUUACUUGACAGAAGGACCUUUACAUGGCAGCUAACAGUGCUUUUUGCUGACCAGGAUUGGUUUAUAUGAUUAAAUUAAUAUUUGCUUAAUAAUACACUAAAAGUAUAUGAACAAUGUCAUCAAUGAAACUUAAAAGCGAGAAAAAAGAAUAUACACAUAAUUUCUGACGGAAAACCUGUACCCUGAUGCUGUAUAAUGUAUGUUGAAUGUGGUCCCAGAUUAUUUCUGUAAGAAGACACUCCAUGUUGUCAGCUUUGUACUCUUUGUUGAUACUGCUUAUUUAGAGAAGGGUUCAUAUAAACACUCACUCUGUGUCUUCAACAGCAUCUUUCUUUCCCCAUCUUUCUAUUUUCUGCACCCUCUGCUUGUUCCCUCAUAUUCUGUUCUUCCGACUCCUGCUAACACACAUGCAACAAAAAAGGGAAGGGAGUGCUUAUUUCCCUUUGUGUAAGGACUAAGAAAUCAUGAUAUCAAAUAAACAUGGUGAAACAUUAGAUCUCUUCUUCAUUUAAUAACCCUCCCCCCUUUUUUUCCUUGAAGAAAUGCGUCUGUUCCUUUCCUUGUGAAAUAUUAUCAGUUUCUACCAUUGCUUCUCAUGCUUGACUUUGUUUUACUUUUUGGCUUGGUAUACUAAGAAGCAAAGGAUCUCAUCUAAAUGGAAUUGAAUGGCAGUCCUAGUUUGUUACUUAUGGUGAUGAGAUUUUCAGAUUUGAACUAAUCUAUUUGACGUGAUUUAGAAAGAAUGUAAGUAUUCACACAUCUCCAAACAUUUGUAUUUGUUACUUCUUUUUGUUGCUAAGGUAGCUCCUGUAGUUAUGCAUUGUUGCAAAAAUUUACAAAUGUUUUAAAAGUGUUAACAUCUGUUUUUUUUUAAACGUUAGCCAAAGAAGAAGUCACUAUUUCCAAGUUAGAAACCACCAGAAAUAAUUGAAAUUUUUGAUAUGUUCUAAUCUUCUUUGCAUUUUUGAGAUCUGUGUGAGAGCCCAACCCCACUCCAGGAGCAUCUGUACAGCUUCCAUCUGCCAUCGACCAGGUCCUCUCAUCAAAUUAAAUGGAACAGAAAAUGCUCUAGUGAAACAAAGGAAAUGUGCAAGCAUUUUUCCUUUUUCUAUUAUUCUAUUUCCCUUUUUCCUUUUUGGCCCCCUUAUAAUCCAAACCCCAGCUGAAAGGCUGCAACAACACCAGGUUGGGGAGCAGGUCACCAGGAUCAUAGUUCAGUCAAAAUGACAUCACUCCCUGGAACUAGAUUUCAACUCACUAGUCCCCUGGCCUCAUAACAGGAACUUAUGCAGGUGAGACACAAGAAUGACUUCCUGUGUAGGACUAGUAGGAAAUCUGCAAGUACUUAGAGCUGGCCAUUACAGAACUUCCUUCCAGAAGUGCCCUGUGACAUGAAAGUAGGACUUCACAACUAAGGUGAAGAUCCCUGCCCUACCACAUGAUUUGAGUCUCUUGGAUUCAAAGGACAUUAAUGUCAACAGAUGGUUGCCAUGUCAGUCUGUUGACACAAUUCCAUUGCUUCAGUUUCUCCCCUUUUCUCUCUAUAUGUUUGGUUGGAGCUUGUGCCUAAUGUAAAUACAUCAUUCAUAAUUAGAAUGGACAUUAAUUAUUUUAGUAAUAAACACAGGAUAAAUAGCUUUGGGGUGAUGAACCAGAGUCUGUUUUUAUUUUAUGGUGUGUACAUAUUUUAAGCUGUACUUCUGUGAAUGGUACUGAUUUUUGUGGUUGUUUUUUUUUUAUAUUUUGUUUGUUUAAGCAGAAGAGUGGAAUAUGGGGUCAAAAUCAUAAAAGAAGUUGCCAUGA